AGUUCAUGUUUAAUGGGCACAGAGGUUUUGUUAGGGAUGACGAAAAAGUUCGGGAGAUGGUGAUGGAGAUGGUGAUGGUGAUGGAGAUGGUGAUGGUGAUGGAGAUGGUGAUGGUGAUGGAGAUGGAGAUGGUGAUGGAGAUGGAGAUGGUGAUGGUGAUGGAGAUGGUGAUGGUGAUGGAGAUGGAGAUGGUGAUGGAGAUGGUGAUGGUGAUGGAGAUGGAGAUGGUGAUGGUGAUGGAGAUGGUGAUGGUGAUGGAGAUGGAGAUGGAGAUGGUGAUGGUGAUGGUGAUGGAGAUGGUGAUGGUGAUGGUGAUGGUGAUGGAGAUGGUGAUGGUGAUGGUGAUGGUGAUGGAGAUGGUGAUGGUGAUGGUGAUGGAGAUGGUGAUGGUGAUGGAGAUGGAGAUGGUGAUGGUGAUGGUGAUGGAGAUGGUGAUGGUGAUGGGAUGGUGAUGGAGAUGGUGAUGGUGAUGGUGAUGGAGAUGGUGAUGGUGAUGGAGAUGGUGAUGGAGAUGGUGAUGGUGAUGGAGAUGGUGAUGGUGAUGGUGAUGGUGAUGGAGAUGGUGAUGGUGAUGGUGAUGGUGAUGGUGAUGGAGAUGGUGAUGGUGAUGGUGAUGGUGAUGAUGGAGAUGGUGAUGGUGAUGGUGAUGGUGAUGGUGAUGGAGAUGGUGAUGGUGAUGGUGAUGGUGAUGGAGAUGGUGAUGGUGAUGGUGAUGGAGAUGGUGAUGGUGAUGGAGAUGGUGAUGGUGAUGGUGAUGGUGAUGGUGAUGGUGAUGGAGAUGGGUGAUGGUGAUGGUUGCCUAACAUCAGGAACGUGCUUAAUGCUUCUGAAUUGCACACAAAAAUGGCAAGUUUAAUAUUAUGUGUACUUUAUCACAAUGAAAAAAGCUGCUGCGUGGGCCAAGUUACUUGUGCAGAUUAUUCAGGACAGGGAGUUGACCAACUGCAAAGAGUGAUUGACACCAUCAAAACCAACCCUGACGACAGAAGAAUCAUCAUGUGCGCUUGGAAUCCAAGAGAUCUUCCUCUGAUGGCGCUGCCUCCAUGCCAUGCCCUCUGCCAGUUCUAUGUGGUGAACAGUGAGCUGUCCUGCCAGCUGUACCAGAGAUCGGGAGACAUGGGCCUCGGUGUGCCUUUCAACAUCGCCAGCUACGCCCUGCUCACGUACAUGAUUGCGCACAUCACGGGCCUGAAGCCAGGUGACUUUAUACACACUUUGGGAGAUGCACAUAUUUACCUGAAUCACAUCGAGCCACUGAAAAUUCAGCUUCAGCGAGAACCCAGACCUUUCCCAAAGCUCAGGAUUCUUCGAAAAGUUGAGAAAAUUGAUGACUUCAAAGCUGAAGACUUUCAGAUUGAAGGGUACAAUCCGCAUCCAACUAUUAAAAUGGAAAUGGCUGUUUAGGGUGCUUUCAAAGGAGCUCGAAGGAUAUUGUCAGUCUUUAGGGGUUGGGCUGGAUGCCGAGGUAAAAGUUCUUUUUGCUCUAAAAGAAAAAGGAACUAGGUCAAAAAUCUGUCCGUGACCUAUCAGUUAUUAAUUUUUAAGGAUGUUGCCACUGGCAAAUGUAACUGUGCCAGUUCUUUCCAUAAUAAAAGGCUUUGAGUUAACUCACUGAGGGUAUCUGACAAUGCUGAGGUUAUGAACAAAGUGAGGAGAAUGAAAUGUAUGUGCUCUUAGCAAAAACAUGUAUGUGCAUUUCAAUCCCACGUACUUAUAAAGAAGGUUGGUGAAUUUCACAAGCUAUUUUUGGAAUAUUUUUAGAAUAUUUUAAGAAUUUCACAAGCUAUUCCCUCAAAUCUGAGGGAGCUGAGUAACACCAUCGAUCAUGAUGUAGAGUGUGGUUAUGAACUUUAAAGUUAUAGUUGUUUUAUAUGUUGCUAUAAUAAAGAAGUGUUCUGCAUUCGUCCACGCUUUGUUCAUUCUGUACUGCCACUUAUCUGCUCAGUUCCUUCCUAAAAUAGAUUAAAGAACUCUCCUUAAGUAAA